CUCUUCCCGCCGGCGGCGGAGUCGCUGCCGCUCCGGGUUCCCGUCCCCGCCUCCGAGACCCCCGCGCGCCUCCUCCAGGCGAGCUGCGGGGCGGGAAGGGUCCGGCCACCGUGGGCCGCUGCCAGCCGCGGGGCUGCCGAGGGCCGCGGGCACGGGGCGCUGGCUCCGGGUCUGGCGGCCGCUGAUGGGAGUCGGAGCCCGGGCGGGCGAGCGGCGGCGCGGCGGCCACCAUGGGGAACAAGCAGACCAUCUUCACCGAAGAGCAGCUAGACAACUACCAGGACUGCACCUUCUUCAAUAAGAAGGACAUCCUCAAAUGGGGAAACCGAGGCUCAGAGGGAUUUGGUCACUCCUCCAGGGUCACACAGGCUGUCCACAGUCUGGCUCCGGGGCCCUCCUGCUUAUCCUGCACCCACAGUGAUUGCUGUGUGUGUUUUCUUCAGGAGAAUCCCUUCAAAGAAAGGAUCGUGGCGGCGUUUUCCGAGGAUGGUGAGGGGAACCUCACUUUCAACGACUUUGUGGACAUGUUUUCCGUGCUCUGCGAGUCGGCUCCCCGAGAGCUCAAGGCAAACUAUGCCUUCAAGAUCUAUGACUUCAACACUGACAACUUCAUCUGCAAGGAGGACCUGGAGCUGACGCUGGCCCGGCUCACUAAGUCAGAGCUGGAUGAGGAGGAGGUGGUGCUUGUGUGCGACAAGGUCAUUGAGGAGGCUGACUUGGACGGUGACGGCAAGCUGGGCUUUGCUGACUUCGAGGACAUGAUUGCCAAGGCCCCUGACUUCCUCAGCACUUUCCACAUCCGGAUCUGAGGACACUGCCGAGGCUGUAGGGGCCUAGAAGUCCACCAUCCUGCCCUGCAGUCACAUGGGUGUGGCCUCCAAGCUCCCCAGGAAAGCAGUGGCAGCCUCUGGGGUUUACACCACAAAUAUAUCCUGUGGCCCUUUCAGCAAAAAAAAAACCUUAACCAGGAAGGGGGCCUGUGAAGGUUAGGACCCUUCCCACAGCCCCGCUGUGGUCCAGCCCCGGGACCCAUGGCCUCUCUCCAGGCCCUCCGCACCCCGCCCCAUGCCCCAGUCCUUUCCUACUCCAGAAAUGCUCCCCACCCCCCCAAAGAGGGAAAAGCAGAUAACCCAACAGGAGGUGGUGGGGUCUGACGUGUCCAAGUGCUGGCAGACACCCUGGUCACCCAGGACAGAGCGGAAAAAAAAAAAAGAGGUCAGGGUUUUAACGAGCUAUGCAAUCUUUUUCCAAAACCCAAGGUUGGGCUGCUUCCCACCCCUGCCUGUUCCCCUUCUCCCGGCCUCCUUCACAAUGUGAAGCUGUGGGUGCAGUGGGCCCAAGGGCUCUUGCUCCUGUCUCUGCCUCUGGGUCAUGAGUACCACCCUGCCUGCCUCCCCAACACCGUGGAAUCCUCACUGGUGUGCUGUCCACAGAUUUGUGAACUCCUGGUAGUAAAACACUUUUGCAUCCCUUUGCUCUCCAUGUAUGCUAAUGUUAGGAAAUGUUUGAGGGUA